AACCUGCGCGGCGGCCGCUCCUGCAGCCGCGGCCGCCGCCACUGCCGGGAGAGCUCGAUGGGCUUCUCCUGCGCGCCGCCCGGUGUCUGGCCGAGUCCAGAGAGCCGCGGCGCCUCGUUCCGAGGAGCCAUCGCCGAAGCCCGAGGCCGGGUCCCGGGUUGGGGACUGCAGGGGAAGGCAGCGGCGGCGGCGGCGGGAGCCCCACCGGGGUCUGGGACUGGGGAACUGCCUCCGGCUUCACGAUGCCAGUAUGGACAGAAUAGCUUAUGAUGCUUAUCCCCACCCACCACUUCCGAAACAUUGAGCGGAAACCAGAAUACCUCCAGCCAGAGAAGUGUGUCCCACCCCCCUACCCUGGUCCUGUGGGAACCAUGUGGUUUAUCCGUGACGGCUGUGGCAUCGCCUGUGCCAUCGUUACCUGGUUUCUGGUCCUCUAUGCGGAGUUCGUGGUCCUCUUUGUCAUGCUGAUUCCAUCUCGAGACUACGUGUAUAGCAUCAUCAACGGAAUUGUGUUCAACCUGCUGGCCUUCUUGGCCCUGGCCUCCCACUGCCGGGCCAUGCUGACGGACCCCGUGAGAACCUGCACGGAAAUGGCCUUCACUUUGCUUGGGCGAGGUGCAUCUUUUCCUGAAAAGCUGGACAAGCCUGUUUCAGGCCGCAGCAAGUGCCUCUUGGGGGCAGUGCCCAAAGGAAAUGCCACUAAAGAAUUCAUCGAGAGUUUACAGUUGAAGCCUGGGCAGGUGGUGUACAAGUGCCCCAAAUGCUGCAGCAUCAAGCCCGACCGAGCCCACCACUGCAGUGUUUGUAAGCGGUGCAUUCGGAAGAUGGACCACCACUGUCCCUGGGUCAACAACUGUGUAGGCGAGAACAACCAGAAGUACUUCGUCCUGUUUACAAUGUACAUAGCUCUCAUUUCCUUGCACGCCCUCAUCAUGGUGGGAUUCCACUUCCUGCAUUGCUUUGAAGAAGAUUGGACAAAGUGCAGCUCCUUCUCUCCACCCACCACAGUGAUUCUCCUUAUCCUGCUGUGCUUUGAGGGCCUGCUCUUCCUCAUUUUCACAUCAGUGAUGUUUGGGACCCAGGUGCACUCCAUCUGCACAGAUGAGACGGGAAUAGAACAAUUGAAAAAGGAAGAGAGAAGAUGGGCUAAAAAAACAAAAUGGAUGAACAUGAAAGCCGUUUUUGGCCACCCCUUCUCUCUAGGCUGGGCCAGCCCCUUUGCCACGCCAGACCAAGGGAAGGCAGACCCGUACCAGUAUGUGGUCUGAAGGACCCCGACCGGCAUGGCCACUCAGACACAAGUCCACACCACAGCACUACCGUCCCAUCCGUUCUCAUGAAUGUUUAAAUCGAAAAAGCAAAACAACUACUCUUAAAACUUUUUUUAUGUCUCAAGUAAAAUGGCUGAGCAUUGCAGAGAAAAAAAAAAGUCCCCACAUUUUAUUUUUUAAAAACCAUCCUUUCGAUUUCUUUUGGUGACCGAAGCUGCUCUCUUUUCCUUUUAAAAUCACUUCUCUGGCCUCUGGUUUCUCUCUGCUGUCUGUCUGGCAUGACUAAUGUAGAGGGCGCUGUCUCGCGCUGUGCCCAUUCUACUAACUGAGUGAGACAUGACGCUGUGCGUGGAUGGAAUAGUCUGGACACCUGGUGGGGGAUGCAUGGGAAAGCCAGGAGGGCCCUGACCUCCCACUGCCCAGGAGGCAGUGGCGGGCUCCCCGAUGGGACAUAAAACCUCACCGAAGAUGGAUGCUUACCCCUUGAGGCCUGAGAAGGGCAGGAUCAGAAGGGACCUUGGCACAGCGACCUCAUCCCCCAAGUGGACACGGUUUGCCUGCUAACUCGCAAAGCAAUUGCCUGCCUUGUACUUUAUGGGCUUGGGGUGUGUAGAAUGAUUUUGCGGGGGAGUGGGGAGAAAGAUGAAAGAGGUCUUAUUUGUAUUCUGAAUCAGCAAUUAUAUUCCCUGUGAUUAUUUGGAAGAGUGUGUAGGAAAGACGUUUUUCCAGUUCAAAAUGCCUUAUACAAUCAAGAGGAAAAAAAAUUACACAAUUUCAGGCAAGCUACGUUUUCCUUUGUUUCAUCUGCUUCCUCUCUCACCACCCCAUCUCCCUCUCUUCCCCAGCAAGAUGUCAAUUAAGCAGUGUGAAUUCUGACUGCAAUAGGCACCAGUGCCCAACACAUACAGCCCCACCAUCAUCCCCUUCUCAUUUUAUAAACCUCAAAGUGGAUUCACUUUCUGAUAGUUAACCCCCAUAAAUGUGCACGUACCUGUGUCUUAUCUAUAUUUUAACCUGGGAGACUGUUGUCCUGGCAUGGAGAUGACCAUGAUGCUGGGGUUACCUCACAGUCCCCACCCUUUCAAAGUUGACAUAUGGCCAUCCCAUUGGCCAGAAUCCACAGACACACCUAAGCCUGUGGCACUGGGACAGAAUAGAUUUUCCAUUUGAGAGGCACUUCCUGUGUCAGUCUUGUUUGAAGGAGGUGGUGAUGGUGGAUAGAGGUGAAGGAGGUAGGGAGUGCCCUCCAAGUGCAAAAAUAACAAAUAUGAUUAUUGACCAUCGGGGAAUUCUCACACAUUGAUUUGUUUUUUAAGCAAUUGCCAGAAACCCCCUUUUUUAGCUUUUGCUUGGGGUGGGGGUAGGAGUUAAGGUUUAUUCAAUCCUGUCCUGGGUAGGGCGAAAGUUAAUCUAGCCAUGUGAUUUUUCAGAAAAGUAAGUGGAACAUGCUGCCACUUUUCAAUUCUGUCAGUGCUUCCACAUGGAAACAAAAUGCAAUAAAAUUUUUCCAAAACCUGUUCUGAUUUAGCUCUCUCUUGAGGUGUUACCCUUAGUGGGAGGCCGACUAUCCACAAUCUACUUGAGUUUUCUCUGGUUGGGUGUUUGUUUCAUUGCUCUGUCUCUUGAAUGAGGAUACUUUAUUUUUUUUGUUUUAAAAUGCAUUUAUGGUCCCUCUCUUGAACCAGCUUGCCCCACCAGGCCUCUUUCCUUUGCUUUCUGCAGCCUGAAUCAAUUCCUUUGUGCUGAUGGGCUCUCCUAAGAGCUUUCCUGAGUCAGUUAACUUUACCUCGUGUCUACGGUGCUAUUCAUGCGAUACGGGCGAGGCUGAGAUGCUAAGAUUAAAAAGAAAAGAAUGCUGUUUUAGAUCAAGUUGAUAGCAUUUGUUUUCCAUAUGCUUUUUUAAAAUUUUUUCAUAACAUACAGCUCAGUUAGGUGUAUGAAAGAAGUGUUAUUGUAUUAAAUAACUAGAGCAGGGCUACAGCUCUGGCCCUCCCCUAGGGGGAAGAGAUUGGUAAUACUCCAUCUUCCAGGGCAUUUUUUAAAGUGAGCCAGGUUAGCUCUUUUCCCCUGGCAUUUCUCAGGAAUGCAGUAGAUAGUGCUGAAGAUGCACUGACUUUUUUUUAGUCCUAAAAAUAGAAACUCCUCCUUUAAAGCUGUGCAUACUAUGCUUAUCUUUCCAAUAGAGUGGGGUUCCUUCAGAUAUCCUAUAGGAUUCUGCCUCUGGUUUUGUAUAGGCCUUGGCUAGAAAGAGUCAAUGUUUCUGAGCUCUCAAACCAGUUGCUCUCAGAAGAUAGGAAUACCCCAAGGUUCCUGGCAUUUUUCCUAUUUCAUUUUUGUUCAGACUGAUAUUUUGCCAAGAGCACAAUGACUGAGGAAUGUAGCCAUCAUUUGCAGGGUAGUGAUUGGUUCCCAGCCUGGCUUCCACACAGGACAGGAAGGGAAAGCAUCCCUGAGCUCUCCUCAGUAUUUCCGGAUGUAAUGAAAGAGGACAUCUUUCUACACAAAGUCAGCCCCAACUUUUGGCUUGGUCACAGGAGUUCUGAUAGUACUGUUUGGUGCACUCAUGGGAAAUUGAACCAGUCGUAGCCACAGUCUUUCAGAGCCUGGGCUCUGGGGAGUGGAAGUGAAAAAUAAAGAUGUGGCUUGUUGGAUUGUGAUCCCCAGCUUGCUUUCCUUCUGUCAACUCUGUCAGGUUUGUGUUCAUAGCAACUAGACUGAAUAUGCAAAAGGCUUAGAUCCAAGCAAAUCUAUAAUCUAUGCAUAUUUGCAUGGGCUUGGUAAUAUCAUGUACACAAAACACAUUUGGGUAGAAGUGCAUGUGCUAAAUCUCCUUUUAGUCCCACCAUUUUGUCUUCUUCAUACUGUACUUCCUCUUUUUUGUUUGAGACAAGGUCUUGCUCUGUCACCCAGGCUGGAAUGCAGUGGCACAAUUAGAGCUCACUGCAGCCUUGAACUCCUGGGCUCAAGUGAUUCUUGUGCCUUGGCCUCCUGAAUAUCCAGGGCUACAGGCACGUACUACCAUGCCUGGCUAAUUUUUUUGUUUUUUAAUAGAGUCAGGGUCUCACUGUGUUGCCCUAGCUAGUCUCAAAUGCCCGGCCUCCAGCAAUUUUCCUGCCUUAGCCUCCCAAAGUCCUGGGAUUACAGGCGUGAGCCACUGGGCCCAGCCCUGUACUUCUUGAAAAAGCCCCAAGUAUUAGCUUUUGCUCAUCUGGCUAGGCCACUUAAAUAGUUAGAAUCCACCGUCCCCUAAUGCAGAAACCGUUUAGGUGAGGUAAAUUAACAAACAUUUUAAGCCGGGCGCGGACACUUCUCACUGUGGACAUCCCUCACGCCUGUAAUCCCAGCACUUUGGGAGGCCGAGGCGGGCAGAUCACGAGGUCAAGAGAUCGAGAUCAUCCUGGCUAACACGGUGAAACCCUGUCUCUACUAAAAAUAUAAAAAAAUUAGCUGGGCGUGGUGGCAGGCGUCUGUAGUCCCAGCUACUUGGGAGGCUGAGGCAGGAGAAUGGCGUGAACCCGGGAAGUGGAGCUUGCAGUGAGCCAAGAUCGCACCACUGCACUCCAGCCUGGGCGACAGAGUGAGACUCCGUCUCAAAAAAAAAAAACAAACAUUUUAAACAUGUAUGUGAGGUUGGCAUUACACAGAAACUCCUCUCCGGGUGGGCUGGGAUGGGCUUUCUCAGCCAGGCUAAUGGGUUUUAAAUUUCUCUCUUUUCAAGACUUGCAGUGCAUCAGCUUAAAGGGUGAGCCAGCCAGUAGAGGGGAAGGCGCCCCACCUAGAAGGUGCCCUUAGAUAUCAAAGAAAUGUGAAAAGAGAAAGAUUUUGCUAGAAUCCUCCUCAAAGGUGUUCUUGAGGUUGCCAGACCAGCAACGUCAACAUCAGCAUCACCUGAGAACUUGUUAGAAAUGCACAUUCUCGGUCCCCACCCCAGGCUACCGAACCAGAAACCGAGCGGGGCCCAGCAGCCCGUGUCUUAACAGCCCUCCAGGUGAUUCUGACUAUCAAGUUUGAGAAUCCAGUUGGGGCUAGCAGGAGUCCCCCCUCAGGUGGUCCCUGAUGCCUGCUGGUGAUAUGGGUCUUGUGUGCUGCUGGGCUCAGCAUAGUGCAGUUGGGGUGUGCUGAUUGUGAGACAGGCACGUGUUCCCUCCGCGGAGAAGCCACUGAGACUGCCUUCCCUCAUAAGCUGCGGCCUCCCCAACAAACAACUGCCAAGACAUCAAAGAAAGUCUGUAUGAAGCAGAUCCAAAUUAUUAGCCUGCCCACCACUCCUUGUGCAUCUCAUCAGUGGAACCCAUCUCUAGACCAAGGGCCCUUUGGGUGAAGAAGCAGCCCGGAAGGGAAAGAGAAAAGAGUAGAACCAAGGGACCUCCAGAUGGGAGCGGCGGCCGGUGAGUAGUCUAGAGCCAGGGGCAUUGUAGCAGCCUGGAUACAUGACCUGAACACGUCUUGACCUUUGCUUUCUACGUGUGGGUUUCAACACCCAUGUGGCUUUUUCUUGUAUUCUUUAAAUAUGUAUCUGGCUUAGGAUCACCUCAUAGAAGAGAAAGAAUUCACAGUGAAGCAGAAACAAGCCACUGACCAGCGUACUCCCAACCUGAACCUUCUUUUUCUCACCCUCUCCCUCAAGUAAACAUCUUGCUGACUUGAGCAGUGUGAUUGCCGUAGCAAAGCAGAGUGGCCCCCAGGGAUCCCGCUCUGUUGGGCCCACAGGAGGAGCCGAUGAAGCUGAUCCAAGGAGUGAGGACAAGCGCUGCAGAGGGACGUUCGCUAAAAGCCUUCUAGGGGCCGCACAUGCUCUAACACGGACAUAAGGAUGCCCUGAAUUUCUGCAGCUGAGGCCAUAUAGUCUGGUGACCAAGUAUUUGGGUCCUGGCUUCAGUCUUUGGUUGAAAUGUCUGCUUGGCUACUUAUUACCGCACCUACUACCAAAAUAUGACCUUGAGCAGUAACUUCUUUAAGCCUCAGUUUUUUCAUCUGAAAACGGGAAUGAUAAUCUAAAUCACAAAGUUAAUGGAAGGAUUAAAUGAGGGUGAUGAAUAGGAAUGUAUAGCGUCUGGCCCUGGUAUGGCUUUAUAAAUGUUAGCUGUGUUGGAGCUGUGCUUUUCAAACCAUUGGUCACAGCCAUUCAUGGUUUGCAACCAGCAUGUUUUUCAAGAAAAAUGUUUAAUGCAUUACAUAUUGCAGGAUAAGUAUUGUUUUAUGAAGCUUAGGGAGUUGUGUGUAUAUGUGUUCUGGAAUGCAACAGAAAAAUGUUUCCUCUUGUGGGUUACAAUAUAGAGGUAUGAAAUCUCUGAUGAGGAGAGACAGUGUUAUCUGGCCCGCUAUGAAGAGACACAUUUGCAUAGGCUGCUCCCUGAGGCUCUGGCUUUCUACAUCUGAUGAUACAGGGAGCAGGGAACAGCCUGUUCUCGUUCUGUGGGGCUCAGCUGAGUCUGUUCUGCACAGACUCUUCCUUCCUCGGGAGCCUUAGUCCUAAUACAUUCAUUUUGGAGUGUUGGUGAGUUUGUUCACAGAUCACAGCUCAUGUGUCACCCAGACUGACCUGGGCCAAAAGGCCCAUCACACACCCUGCAAGAGCUUCUGGUGUCGACUAUGACCCCCUUACCAGGCAUCAACCAUUUUUGUUCGUUCUCUUGAGCCUGAAGCUACUAUUACUGCUCCUCUGCAAACCUCAAGCUUAAGAACUUUGCCUGCAGGAUCCCUUUAAAUCCACACAAAACUCAAAAUUGAGUCCUACCAGGAAAAAGCAGCCCUCAGCCCAUUUUUAUACAUCGGAUUUGUUUGCAAUAUUUUCUUUCUAGACUCAAAAGUCAACACUCCCUGAAAGUUUGUCGACUUUACUGCUGAAGACCUCUGGUAGACAGGCCAGGCUCUGUCUGGAAUACUUUAUGAGGUUGGUGAGGAGGUUGAGUAUAAUCCAAGAGUGCCUAUCUGGGAGCAUGCCACAUGAAUGGCAAAUAAUCAUCCUGUGGGCUCUUGGCUUCAUUCCCCUUCUCUCUGACUGAGCUCAGCCUGGGCACAGUGGUGAUUUGCAGUAGAACUGGAAACCUGUUGGGCAGAAAAAAAGACACUAGUUCUGGUUCCAGUUCUGAUACAUAACAAGCUAGAUGAGCCUUGGCCACCGUCAUGGCCUCUUGGAACUUCUGUUUCUUCCCCAUCUGCCAAUCAUCAAUACUCAUACCCACCUCCUCACAAGGAGGCCAUAAAAACCUAUGGUCAUGGCUUUGAGUCCAAGUCAGUGUGGAUGCAGCCAGUCUGUCAUUUUUGGGUGUUUCCUCUGUAGCCGGGUCUGCCAUAUGGUGAUGUCCCAGCUCUCGUGCUAUGAAGUUAAAGCCUCUUUCUCAACAGGCUGCAGAUGAUCACCCAGGAAGAGAAUGCAGAAUGCCCAAAGCAAACCAUCUCAGCUGGUCACUGCUUCUGUGCCAAGAAGGGAGGCCUGGCGAGGGGCCAGUCAGGAAGCAGCAUGGCAUCACAUGCUCAUGACCCACAUGAAGGUCCCUUUAGACUUGUGUCAACAAGAUCCAUUUUCUGAAACAACUAUUUUUGUUCUGAUUAUAAAAGUAACAUUGGCUCAUUGGUAAAACUUGGAUUGUGUGAGAAGUCUACAGAAAUAAAUACAAAUCCUCUAGAAUUCCAUCCCCAAAAGUAACCACUCAGACAAAUGUUCUAAUGUCAUGUAAAACCAUAUUAAACCAUCUUUUCUAGCUGCAUAGUGUUAUAGAAUCAUUUGCUUAACCAUCAUUAUUGGGCAUUUCUCAUUUCCAGCUUUGCAUUAUUAUAAUUCAGUGUUCAAGUUUGUAUUGCAUAAAUCUUUGUCUCAGAUUAUUGAUUAUUUUUAAACUUUUUGUGAAAUCAGACUUACAAAAAUGUGACAAAAACAGUACAAAGAGUUCCCAUGUACCUUUCAGUCAGUCUCACCAAAGGUAAACAUUUUAUACAACCAUAAUACAAAUAUAAAACCCUGGACAUUGGCAACACCAUACCCUUAACUAAUGUAUGUACCUUAUUCACAUUUCUCCAGUUGUCCCAUUAACACCCUUUUCUGUUCCAGGAUCCCACACUGCAUCAUUUGCGAUGUCUCCUUAGUCUCCUCCAGUUUGUGACAGUUCCUCAGUCUUCCUUUGUCUUUCAUGACCUUGACCCUUUUUAAAAAUCGAGGUGAAAUUCCUGUAACACAAAAUUAGCCAUUUUAAAGUGUACAUUUAAUGCAUUCACAAUGUUUUGUAACCACCAGGUCUGUCUGGUUCCAAAAUCUUUUCAUCAAUCUUUGACCCUUUUGAAGAUUGUAGGGCAGGUAUUCUGUAGGCUGUCCUUCAGAUUGUGUUUUUGAUGUUUUUCUCAUGAUUAGAUUGAGGUUAGGCAUUUGGGGCAGGAGCACUGCUGAAGCAAUGUGUCCUCGUUGCACCGUAUCAGGAGGCAUAUGGUGUUGAUACGUUUCAUUAUUGUGAUGUUAACUUUGAUCAUUGGGUGAAGGUGGUACGUGCAAUGUUUCUUCCCUGCUAUUAAGGUACUGUUUUUCCCUUUGUAAUUGAUAAGUAUCUUAUGAGGAUAUACUUUUGAGAUCCAAUUUUUUUAACUUAGAAUUUAUUCAAAAGUCAAGAAUCUUAAAUCUCUGAAAUGGCGUGGGAAGAAAAAGUGCUAGAUACACAGAGAUCUUUCUUGAGUCAUGUGAAGGAGCAGUGCCCAAGCCCAGCAAACCCACAGCAAAUUCCCUUGGCUUCCAGAAGAGAUGGAGAAAGCAGUGCCCCCAGUGGAGGGUCAAAGGCCUCUGUGCAGGGUGUUGUGGGCCUGGAGAGCUGGCCUGGCCAUGUCUUUACCUCCUCUGGGCAUCUCCCCACCCCAACACCCUUUCUGUGGCCUGGUGGCUGAGUUGCAGCCGACACCCAGAGGCAGGUGAGUUGACAGCUUGGAAGAGGCUGCAGGGUGGAUCUGCUGCAUGAGCAGGCCUGAGCCCAGCCUUACCUCCCCACAGUGGUCCUGUGUGCCCUCCGGCUGCCUAAUGCAUGUUGGCACUUGCUGUACGAGCACCCGCUUCUUCACCUCGCAUGCUGUUUGUGUCCUGCACUCCUUCCUUAACCCCAUCGUCCUUCUGCUGUGUUUGCAGCCCCUAUCUACCCUGGUGGGAGUGGCCAAAAAUAUUUAGGAGGGGAUCACCAGUUUGUAGUGGCCUCAGAGGAUGUGUGGUCCCCCUUAUGCCUCAGCCACUCAUCAGCCUAGCCCCUGCCCAUCAUCUGGCAUUGCACUUGUGGAAGGAAAGAAGGGGAGGGCUGGGUGGUGGGUGGAGAACACGUCAGUCCACCAGGCGGGCCCUGCUUGCUGUGUUCCUCCACGCUGCUGUCCACCCACACCCCAGCAGUCCUCUGAGGGACCUCCCGGGGGUGACCUGGGCCACAACAGACUGCCCACUCAGACCCCAUCUUACCCAUGCCGUGGACACCCCGCCCCCCCCCCCGCCACUGCUAUGCUAUAGCUGGGGGUGUCUAUGUGAGCUGUACAGCCCAGCACCACGCUGACGAUGUUCUUCAUCCCCUUCUCCCUGCAGGGCAUCGAGCGCCUCAAACGAAAGAACCAGCCCAGGGAGCACAUGGGGAGCUGGCAGUCAGUAAAGGAGACCUUUGGUGGGGACUUCUCCCUGAACUGGUUCAACCCCUUCUCCAGACCGUGUCAGCCAGAGAUCCCCAGUGACAAAGACAUGGUGCGGCAGGUGACAUCGCUGUCAGACACCGAAACAAUGGAGGAUCCAUCAGAGGAGACAAAGGACGAGGACUCUGUGGAGGUGACAGAUGAAUAGAUGCUGCUGUGGGGAGAGAAGCAAACACUAAAAAGUGCUGUCAACCUUCAUCCUGGGGUUUUGGCUAAAGGGGCUUAUGGGCAUGGUGCGCUCCCAGCACCCCCAGUGCUUCCCUUAGCCACUCGCUUGGCCUUGCCAUUUCCCCUCCUUCUUCUCUCCAUGUUGGGCCAGGUCUGGGGGUCGGGAGUAGGCUGGGGACAUCAGAGGAGGAUGGGGGCUUUCUCAGAGUUCAUCUAAGAAGAGUCUGCACUGAGACGGCUCAUCAAGAACCGUUCUCCAAGACUGGGUGGCUUUCACAUUCUCCGCCCAGCAAAGGGAGCUUUUGAACAGGGCAUCCCAGGGGCAGAAAAGAGCUUGCCUUUGGCUUUCCCCAGGAUUUCUGUCUUCUCUUGGGAAGGCUGGGCCCCUGGCUCCUGGCUUUGAGAAGUAAGGUUGUGACAGAAGGACCGGGCAGGGCUUGCCUUGGGGACCUGGGUUGGGACACUGACAUCAGGGGAGACUAGCCUGGAAAGACUGCAGAGCUGCCAGCUACUCCCUGGAAAGGGCUUCCCCAUGCUGCCUGCCGAAAUUAGGAGGUAGAGGUGGCUGCCACAUCUACCUGCAAGGGCCAGGCAUGGUUCAAAGAGGACCCUGCAUUAAGCUCUACACACACAUGUGCAGGACAUGUCCAGCAUGGACAGAGCCAGAGUUAAGACAGUAGCACCGAAAAUGAGCCCCCAUUCCACAGACACUGGAGUCUUCACUGAGCGAGACAGCUGGGAGCUGUCCUGCCUGUGGCUACAUAUCUAGCCAUUCACAGAUGUGGAUAUGGGAAGGACCUCUUUGGAGCUACUGGGGACUCCCUAACCACUCGCAUGAGAACUUAAUUGAAUGUUACCUCUUGGAGGGAGUCUAAUAACACAUGUAGGUAGAACUGACCAUAAACCCUGCCUGUGUGUUUGAAAAGGCCAGUUCUCCCAAAUUGGUGCCCAUCUUGUCUCUGAAAAGAUGGGUGAUGGCCAGGGUCUGCUGAUUGAUGAAUCAGAUGAAUCAGGAAGAUAGACAAACACACACACACACACACACACCCCACCAGGAUGAGUCUGCCCUCUAUUCACCCCAUUUGAAGCCUGUGGUGUCUGUGACCACUGCUGAAGGUCUGAGCAGCGUUCUGGUGCUCCUAAACCCCAUUCCAGUGGUUGCUGAAGCAGCAUCUUCUGCACAAAGCCCAACAGAAGGGUUCUUAUCCCCGUUUGGUAUAAGAAGUGGAUUCACCACCCACUCCCUCCACGUGCCUUUGUUCCUCUCUUUGGCCCAUUUCCCCAGCGUCUACUGGCGUCAGGAUUGGCAGGAGCACAGGCACUCAGCAGAGCAUGCCCCUGCAAGACCUCAGUGUUAGGGCCCCCCUUCCAGCUCCAGGCAAAAGGGCAUGAGUCCUGGCCCCAAGGGGCCUGUGGCUGCAGUUCAGAGGAGAAGAAGGUCAGUGUUUGGAGGUGCAGCCUCAGGAUGCUGAGAAAGGAAACUGGCGACCGUGAGAAAGAAAAGAGCCAAGCAGCAUCCUGGUUCUUGGACAGCAUCUUUGGACACUCUGUGAAGGGCAACGAUCCUGCCAGAGACCGUCUCUCUACAACUGAUGACCCACUAGGGCCUGGGGUUAAUUGCUCAAAGGGCCCAGUGUUCACAAAGCCACCUCUGCCCUAACCCUUGCCAGAGCUCUCCAACUAUGACCCACGAGAGGGGUGAUGGUGGGAUUCUAACAUCAACAGAGCAACCAGAAAGACAUUGGGCCUCCCACACUCAGGCUGCAGGCCCACUUUCUUGGUCCUUAUCAGCUUUAAUAUUUAUUAAUGACGACAUAGGAGCCCGAGUCAGCUGUAAAGGCCAUUAACUUGCAAUCUGGACAGGAAGUUGACGCUCACCACUUUGGGUAAGAGCUGCUCUGACUGUAGGGCCCCCUAUUUGUUGUCCUAACCCAGAAGCAGCUCUGGGCUGCCAGGAUGGUGGAUGGAAUACCAGAGAGUUCACACUAGGGAGGAAGCAAUGCCUGCCCCCUGGAGUCUCCUAGGGGGCAGCAGUUAGAAUAAGGGAAGAGGAUUUGCUGGUCACUGUUUGCUGACAUGGGUUUCCAUGGUGAGUUCAGGCCUGAGGACAGCAGUGUCUGCAAAACCACAUGGCCCUUGAGAAAUGUCCUUGCACAUUGGGCUUCAAACUCCUCUUCUAGGGAAUCCAUCUUGGCCUGAAAGCAGAGGUACAACACCAGCCCCAAAGGCAAUUCUGUUUUCAGAUUGGUUGCUCUGGAAAGGAAGGCUGGGGUGAGGGGGCAUUUUACUUGCACAGAGGCUGACCCUGCCUCCCCUCUUCACUGACCCCAUCUCCAAGGUAGACCUCAGCCAUGUCAGUCCCUGUUCUGGGAGGUGCUGGGCUGGGCCACAGCCAGGGUUAUGUAGGUAAUUAACCUGUCCAACCCUGAGCCUCGCCUCCCCACACCAGCAACACAGUGGUCUCUCUGUGGUGACCAUUCACAGCAUAACAUUCUGCUUAGCCUCAGACUGAAAGCAUUGCAACUGAUGUCAAAACCAGAUGAGAUCUUACAGGGAGAGAGAUUGGGUGCAAUUUGCCUCUUUCUUUGAAUAAAAAGCUCUUUGCUCACCCUCA